CUUCUGUUUUAGAAGCAUUUAUAUUCUCUUAAAGUCUGAUGGUUAGGUUUCUAACUUUUCCAGUAUUUGGAUUGGUAAAUGUACUACUUAAGUUACAUAAAUGCUUUAUUAUUGGUAAUGGCACAUAUAAAAUCUCAAUGCAUUUAUAUGACUCUCUAGUAAUUUGUUAUACAAAGAGUACAGAAAACAGUGAUUUACCAUAGACUAUUGUUUACAUCUGAAUCUAUUUGUUCAACUCUUUUAUUACCAUUGCCUUGUUUGGCUCAUAUAAAUUUUAUUUAAUUUUUCUUUCUAACUAAUCACAAUGAUACCAAAUUGUAGUAUAUAGUUUUAUUUGUAGCAUAGAUUGCUCUCUAAAAAUAUGUACCAUGAGUACAUGUGUAAAUCAAUGAACAUCAACUUAAACAGUAGCUAUUUCAUGUGAACUACACACAUUCUUGUCAAGAAACAGGAGUAAAUGGCUGAGGCCCAGGCAUAAUUCCUUGGAAGUGACAAUGCCAAAAUGCCCAAGGAAGCUCUUGGCAGGGCUACUCAUUUGUUUUCACAUAUUUAUCUAUUUGUUCCCUUGGUUUCAAGGCUUUAAACAGAAAUUCAGAGCAUUUUCAUGGUAUCUGGGCAUCAUUACAAUAUUUACUAAAAGAGAAGUCCUAAACAUGGUCAUUUUAUGGGAGAAAUCAGUAGCACAUGGUGUUUAUGCAAUGUUAUAUAUGAUUUUACUCAUUAUGCCAACUGUAUUAAGGGGAUUCCAUCUUUCUUUGGGCCCUCAUCAGGCUACCACGAUAUACAAUGAGUGGUAUACUUAAGCUCUGGCUGAAUUGUUCUGUAAUGUAAUCUGACUCAAGGAGAACAAAUGGAGAGGGUCUUUGUCAUUCUACUGUGUCAUGUGAAUUUUCUCUGUUUCUGGAGUCUAAGUUGUUCUGUUUUUCACCUGCUAUUUGAGAAAUUUUUUACAAUUUUCGUGUCAUAAGCCAGAAUGCAAUGGGAUGAAUAUGGAGCCUUUCUUUUUAUACACUCUCUUGAAACUCUUCAUGAAAAGCUUUCUUAUUGAAUUGUUUCAUUCUAGCUUGAAUAUCGAAAUGGAAUGUGUUACGAUAAAUUCAUAAGUACGUUUCUAUUAUUAUACUAUUUAUAUAGUUAUGACACAUUGUGAAUUGAAUGAAAGGUCUUAUAAAAUUCUGAAAAGCUGUGCUGUUGCUUGUGUAUUAUUUAUUUAUAUCUCUAAAAUUAUCCACUGACUGCAAAUUGUCCGUAAGGGACAUAUUCAAUGUAAAACAAUCAUUCCCAGAACUAAAAAAGGUCUAAAAAUUUCUUUUGAAUUUUCUUUCUACUACAAAUUUUUGCAUAAGAACAGAAACAGUAACUUCUUUCUAAAACAACAAUGGAAUCUCAAUAUCAAAAUUAGUCUGGUUAAGUACAGCAUGACUGUAGGCCUAGCUGCUUGGGAGGCUGAGGUGGGAGGAUCACUUGAGGCUCAGAGUUUGAGGCUGCAGUGUACUAUAAUAGUGCCUAGGAACAGCCACUGUACUUGAAGCUGGUCAGCAUAAUGAGACCACAUCUUUCUCAAAAAAAAAAAAAUCUGAUGCUCAGUAUCAAUCAUUUAAAAAUAAAUGAAUGAAUGAUCAUGGGACAGAAAAAUGAUAAAUUCUGUAUUCAAUCUACAUUUGAACUUAUAUUUUUGUUACAUCUCUGCAAAUUAUUUUCAUGGGUUUAAGUAUUUUUAAUUCAUUUUAUUUUUAUUUGCAAAAACAUUGCACAUACAUCUAAUUUUUAAAAAUUUUCUGGGAUCAUAAGACUACAUGGUUAAAAUAUUCUAUUAUACUUUUAUAGCAGAUUCAAUCAAAAUAAGAUAAUUACUGAAUAAAAUGUAAACAUUGACUAGAAAUGUCCCUUUUAAUGAAAUCAAUAGGCAUCCUGUAUAUCUAUAGAUGAAUAAUUUUUAGUGCUAGUUAAGCAGAUACAGGUUUUUGUCUCAAUUAUAUUUCUUUCUUGGUUUUUCUUGGUUUUUAAUUGAGGUACGUGCUGAGUAACUUGUUCACAUAAUAAAGUAGAUGACAGUGGAAAGUAUUUUAUUUUCAGUAUUAGUCAAUUAUUUGAACUUGCCAAAAAUCACAUAAUGAUUUAUUAUCAAAAAUUAUUUGUAAUGAUCUGUGGACUGACAAUUCACUUGAAUCUUCCCUCAAUAUUGUGAAGAGCAGAAAAUUGGAAACCAUCUGAUUAACAAAAAGAUUAUUUCUAGUCAAUAAACUUAGCAUUUCUGAGAAGUGUCUCAAAAACAUUUACCAAAACUUAAAAAAUGAAAAUAACUAUACUGCCUUUUUAUCAUUUAGAGGCAAAAAAUCAAAAAAUUAAAAUACAGGUAUACUUCUACUUAUUGCAUUUCACUUUAUUGCACUUUGCAAAUACUGCAUUAAUUACAAAUUGAAGGUUUGUGGCAACCCUGCCUUCAGAAACUCUGUUGGCACCAUUUUUCAUGACAGCAUGUGCUGACUUUGUGUCUUGUGUCACAUUUUGGUAAUUCUCACAGUAUUUCAAACUCUUAUUGUUAUUAUAUCUGUUAUGGUUAUCUUUGAUGUUGCUAUUAUAAUUGUUUUUGGGUGCCAUGAACUGUGCCCAUAUAAGAGGGUAAGUUUAAUGUUGUGUGCAUUAUCACUACUCCAUAGACCAGCUGUUCUGCUAUCUCUCCCCCUCUCCUAGGGCCUCUCUACUGUCUGAGAUACAACAGUAUUGAAAUUAGGCCACUUAAUAAACCUACAGUGGCUUCUAAGUGUUCAAGUGAAAGGAAGAGUUGCAAGUCUCUCAUUUGAAAUCAAAAGCUAGAAAUGAUUCACCUUAAUGAGAAAGGUGCUGAAAGCACAGGCUGAAAGCUAGGUGUCUAGCACUAAGGUUAGCCAAGUUGUGAAUGCAAAGGAAAAGUGAAGAAAGUUUUAGAAGUUUGGAUACAAGAUCAAACCACCCACAACAUUCCCUAAGCCAGAGCCUAAUCCAGAGCAGGGCCCUAACUGUCUUCAAUUCUACUGAAGCUUACAGCUGCCGUACAUAAUGACUCCUCUGAUGAAUCUGGGAAAAGGAGAUGGAAAAUCUUCUGGAAAGGAUUUGCUAUUCUAGAUAACAUCACGAUCAUUCACUGUUAUGGGAGGAGGUCAAAAUACCAACAUUAACAGAAGUUUGGAAGAAGUUUAUUUCAAUCCUCAUGGGUGACUUUAAGAGGCUCAGGACUUCAGUGAAGUCCUGUAAGUAGUGUUUUGGUGAAUAAAUACGGCAGCCGGCCGGUGGUGAUAGCAGGAGGCUUAUUAUGCUGUCUUGGAAUGGUGUUGGCCUCCUUUAGUAGCAGCGUGGUACAGCUGUACCUCACUAUGGGAUUCAUUACAGGUUUAGGUUUAGCCUUCAACCUGCAACCCGCCUUAACCAUAAUUGGCAAAUACUUCUAUAGGAAGCGACCCAUGGCAAAUGGAUUGGCCAUGGCAGGAAGUCCUGUUUUCUUAAGUUCAUUGGCUCCUUUCAAUCAGUACCUUUUUAAUACUUUUGGCUGGAAAGGAAGCUUCCUGAUUUUGGGAAGUCUACUUUUGAAUGCCUGUGUGGCUGGUUCCCUCAUGAGACCCCUUGGACCCAAUCAAACCACUUCUAAGUCUAAAAAUAAGACUGGCAAAACAGAAGAUGAUUCAAGCCCAAAGAAAAUCAAAACGAAGAAAUCAACUUGGGAAAAAGUUAAUAAGUAUUUAGAUUUCUCCCUUUUUAAGCAUAGAGGAUUUCUGAUAUAUCUGUCUGGAAAUGUCAUUAUGUUCCUAGGUUUUUUUGCCCCCAUUAUAUUCUUGGCUCCAUAUGCUAAAGACCAAGGAAUUGAUGAGUACUCGGCAGCUUUUCUGCUAUCUGUUAUGGCUUUCGUUGAUAUGUUUGCUAGGCCUUCUGUAGGAUUAAUUGCAAACUCCAAAUAUAUUCGACCUCGAAUUCAGUACUUCUUCAGUUUUGCAAUCAUGUUCAAUGGAGUGUGUCACCUCUUGUGCCCACUGGCACAGGACUACACAAGCCUGGUAUUAUAUGCUGUAUUUUUUGGCCUUGGAUUUGGGAGUGUUAGCAGUGUUCUCUUUGAAACUCUCAUGGACCUCGUGGGUGCACCAAGAUUUUCCAGUGCCGUCGGACUUGUCACAAUUGUGGAGUGUGGCCCAGUUCUUCUUGGCCCUCCUCUUGCAGGUAAAUUGGUGGAUUUAACUGGAGAAUAUAAAUACAUGUACAUGUCCUGUGGGGCUAUUGUGGUAGCAGCAAGCGUGUGGCUGCUCAUUGGCAAUGCUAUCAACUAUAGAUUGCUUGCAAAGGAAAGGAAGGAGGAAAAUGCAAGGCAGAAGACCAGAGAAUCUGAACCCUUGAGCAAAUCUAAACAUUCGGAAGAUGUUAACGUCAAAGUUUCAAAUGCACAGAGUGUAACCUCAGAAAGAGAAACUAACAUUUAACAAGAAUCACAUCUCUGAUUUCAGUGUUUAUGACUUUAUCUAGGAGUUUGUUUUUCAUUUUGUUUUUUUAAAGUAUUAGAAAAGGUUUUAGCUGAAAUGAGGAGUCACAAUUAAGGAUGGAGGUGAUAUUUUCCUCAAUGGCAAAUUUUAAAUUAGUUUUUAAAAACUUACUUAUUUGGGUAGUUAAAUUUUGAGAUUAUGCAUAGAAAGAAUCCAUGCUAUAGGUUUAUUUCCAUACCUGACUCUGGGUGUGGUGGUUAAAAUACUAAUUUUAAAGUCUUCCAGUGACUUUCGGUCUUGGUUAUAUGGAGAAUUCUGAAUCCCAAACCCCUGGUUUAAGUAGGUAGAAGGAGGAUGCCUAAUCCUACAAAGUGACCCUUUAUACAUUUCAUUUUUUAUUUGAUAUUAAAGUAUGAGAUAGAGUUGAGAGACAAUUAAUUAUCCCCUCUUACACACAAACACACAUACUCCCACAUACUUACCCACAUGUACACAGAGUAUCUGGAGAAUAAAACCCAAAUUCAAAAAAAAAAAUGAUAAUUUAUUUUUAAGGUAAAAAUAAUCCAUGAAGAUAAAAGAAACAUAUGUCUGCGUGCUACUUUACAAUGUUGGUUUUAAAGAUAAGCACAUGGGUAAAAAUGAGGGUGAUCCUUAUUCAAAAAUAACAUCUGACUACUAUAAAAAUAUUUGCAUAUAUAAGUUUGACAAAGAAAAGAAAAUCAAUGUUAAACCAUUAAAUCUGAGCACUGUUAGACUUGAUUAAUCCAUGCACAUGAUUUUUUUUGAGUAGGGAGCAUUAGUACCUGGUGCUAGAGAAUAGAACCCUCAAAUAAUUUUUAGAAUUCUUACCUAAUAUGUAAAAGUCUGCAUGACUCUUAACAAUGAGUCACAUCCAUUGAUUUUACAGGGAUUUUAGUUCGUAAUCCAGAAAGUAAUAAUCAGGGAUUUUAUUUUAAUCAGGCAUCAAUCCAGAUUCACUGUUAUACUGAAAUAUCAAAGUAAAAUCCUAGUUGGCAGGAUUGUAAGUAGACCGAAUUCUAAUUUUUCCCAACACAUAGUGGUAAUUGGAGGUUACUGUUAUGAAUACUCCAUCUGACUACGACUAAGAGAGUGAGGGGUGGUUUUAAUGAACCCUCUAAGCUCUCUCAGUUCCUUCCCUUCCACAAAAUGCAAGAGCAAAAGCAAACUACAAACAGGCCUUGUGCUCAACCACUGGAAAUGCCUCCUGGGAUAAGAAUGGCAGCACUUGAAAAUUCUGCCCUCUACUGAUGAGACUUCCUGCUGCCUUUGGACAUAACUAAGCCAGGAAACUUUAAAAGCCUUCUAGAAAUAGAGGCACUGUAUGACUUGCAAUCGUAGGUAUAGUUUAUAACCUGAUAGCAAAAAACUUGAAAUAUUGCAGCCCAGUUUAAUUCAGCACUUUCCCAUUUUCAUAACUAUGUGAAAACAUCUGGGAAUUUGAAUCACUCCUGAAUACAGAGGCAUAUUCUUUUUAAACUAUAAAUACCAUUUUGAGUGAGAAAGUACUUUUAAACAAGAAAGAAAUUGUACAUUAUGACUAAAGUUAUAAAUACAAUAUUUAUAUCUAUAAAUCUGAAGUUUAACAUGAUUAAUUUAAAAAGUAUUUAGUGCUUGACAAAGUAGUGUCACUCUUAAGAUGUCAAAGGGAAUUAGCCAUUUUUUUUAUUGUAAUAAAGGCAGGUGCUAUUUUUUUCUGGUGAGAUUGCACCUGGAUACCAGGCUUUUGUAAUAGUUAACAUUAAACAUUUGAUUCAUAAAGUUAAUUCACUGCUUAAGCAUGUGGCUCAUAUUUAGGAAGCUAUAUAAAAUUCAGUUUUUCAUUUAACAUUUGCUCUUUUGCAUAUGAAGAGAUAUUUGUAUUUUUCAAAUGUUAAGUAAAACAAGAUGUGCCAAUAUCAUAGGUAAAUAAAUUAGGGAAAAUGUGGGACUUUAUGGCUGUUUUUAAUUUAGUUUCACCCGAUCUUGAUUCUUGAAUUAGCUAUGUUUAUAUUUUUAGUUCUUUUUUAUUCAACUCAGAUUUGUCAAGAAAUGUAACCUCUAAAUUGUGUAGUACCUCUCCAAUCAUAAAUUUUCAAAAAAAAAUUCUACUUUCCAAAAAGUGUCUUGAAUUCUCUGAAAAGGCACAUUAAACUAAUAUGAACAUCAGAUACCAGGGGGAAAUAAAUGGCAAAGUAAUAAUCAUGAGGUUUUAGGUCAAAGACUACAUUAUAUAUAUUUUUUAUUACCUUCUAGUAGAGACAUCCUCCUGGGUGCAUUUCAGUGGCCUUCUCCAGGGAGGAGGUUUAUUUACUUACUGAUGAGUUUCUCGUCACGUCAAAACCAGUUCACAUUUGUCUGGCUGCUCUUUGGUUGUCUUCAUUCGUUAUUUAUUUCUAACACUGUAUUAAAUUGUUAGAAAAGAAAGUAAAACUUGCACAUUCAAAGCACAUGAUUUGUACAGUCACACCUGGCAGUAGCACUGCACAGUUACAAAUAUGCACACACGUUAACUGCUAUGCAUAAAUAUUGACAGUUAAACCAGAACACAAUUGAAACAGUGACAUAAAUACCUACAGGAUUCAGAAUUGUUCCAGGGUAAUAUAAAUUAUUCUACUUGUUCACUCUCCCCACCCUCUUGAACUUGUUAGAAGAUUUGCUGCUUUAGCAGAAUCUUUCCAAGAUUGAGAAAAGUGUAUCAACCUAGGAUUUUCAUUACUAUAUAGUCACAUAAAUGGAGGAGGAGAUAUAUUUGGCUUCUGCCUCUGCAACAAUUAGUAUGAACAUAUUUCUUUCUCUAGGGAAUAAUAGGUUUUAAACAUUUGAGAUAUCAUGAAGCAAAGUCAGGGUAUACCACUACAAUCCCCACUAAUCUCUAUUCCCACAUUAUGAAAUUGUACAGAAGAAAGGGUGUCAUUAAAUCAAGGUAUCCAGAUAAUUCAUGGCUACUUUAACUAUUUUUUCAUUCGUGUUAACUGAGCCCCCCAUAUUUUUUACUACUUAACCUUAAAUAUGCCAUCACUAAUUUAUGAAUAGAACAUUGUGUUUGCACUUUUCCUGACCUAUCCUCACCCCCUUUCCUGAUCCUUUUUGCAUUCACCUAGCACACCUUAAGAGACAAAAAAUCAGGUUUUAGUGUAUUUCACAUUGGAAGACAUGAUGUUUUCUCAGUAUAAAUCUACAGGACUCAUAAACAAUCACUUUUUUGGUGCCAAGUUUCAACCCUUUAGCUCAUGGACUCAUUGGCCUCAGCCUAAUACUAAGAAACAAGUAAAAUAAUUAGAUUUUCUAUGUUUGAAUGUGCACUUUAAAAAAUCUAGAUAAUUUAUACUCAUUCUUUUCUGGCUGUACAACAUGACAAUCAAGAAUAUAGAAAAGAAGACUAAAAGAUAUAUGAUAUAAAUGUAAGUUUUUAUGUAGAUGACAUAAAUAUGAAGAGAUAUUCUUGGUCAGUUGGUUGAAACAUUUUUUAUCUAAAACACCUUUAAAAAAUCCCUUUCAUAUGUAGAAUGUGGAAGGCUUUUAAUAAAACAAAAAUUAUUAUUUUUAGGCUUAAUUUAAUAGGGAGAUUGGAUGCAUAGUGGAAAGGGAACUAAUAUUUAUAUGUUAUGCAUUUUGCUUAUGUAAUGCCUUUCAAUAUGAAAACCAAAACCAUGGCAGAAUUAUUACUAGCUUGAUAUGACAGAUGAGUGAAAACAAAAAACAAGCUCAGCAGACUACCCAAAGUUAAAAGGUAGUAUGAACCAAAAUUAAAACUCAGGUUUACGUAACCAGAAAGAUCCCCGAGGUGUUCACUACCGUGCUGCCUCCCAAUAGAGGCCAGAGAAGCAAAGGAAGAUAAAAUAUAGGUACAAAAAAGAUACAUCCUAUAUAGUAAAACAAUUAGGUUUAACUGUAACUUGUAUUAUGAUUUAUUUAGUGUUUAUUAGAGAACUGCAUUUGCUAGAACCUGAAUAUGUAAUUUCUUUCUUUCUUUCUUUUUUUUUUUUUUUGAGACUGAGUCUCGUUCUUGUCGCCCAGGCUGGCGUGCAGUGGCACAAUCUCGGCUUACUACAACCUCUGCCUCCCAGGUUCAAGCAAUUCUCCUGCCUCAGCCUCCCGAGUAACUGGAAUUACAGGCAUGUGCCACCAUGCCCGGCUAAUUUUGUGGCUUUUUUUGUUUUGUUUUGUUUUGUUUUGUUUUAGUAGAGAUGGGGUUUCUCCUUGUUGGUCAGGCUGGUCUUGAACUCUGACCUCAGGUGAUUCACUCGCCUCUGCCUCCCAAAGUGCUGGGAUUACAGGCGUGAGCCACUGCGCCCAGCCUUGAAUAUGUAAUUUCUGAUUGCCUGCUUUUCUCCCCAAUGCAAAUUAUCUCAAAUAAUGAUAAUUAUUACAUAUAGACAUAAUUACUUCAAUAUGACUCUUUUUCUCAUAAAAAUAAUGACAUAUUUGAGUCAGGCAUAAUACAUUUUUUCUGAGGUUGGAGUUAGCAGGAAAAUGUUAUCUUUUAUGAAUAAAUAAUUCCCAGAUUGGUUGCUACAUAUCAUGAUUCAAAAAGUAAAAUAAUUACCUGGAUGUGGUGAUGUGCACCUGUAGUCCCAGCUACUCGGGAGGCUGAGACGAGAGGGUCAUUUGAGCCCAGGAAGUUGAGGCUUCAGUGAGCUAUAAUGGCCCCACUUGCAGUCCAGCCUAGGCAAUAGAGUGAGAAUCUGUCUCUAUUAAAAAAAAAAUAAAAUGUUCUUACUAGAAAACAUUAUAUUUAGAAUUUUAGUGAUUAUUCCAUUUAUAAUAUUAUCCGUAGCUACCAAAAAAAAGAUUAUAAGAUACAAAUGAUUUGGUUUACCCAUACAGUUACAUAUUAAUUUUCAUCAUUUAAUACAACUUACCCUACACCGUAGCUUAUUUUUCAAGUUUCUCUGAACAUCUUUGUUGUCAUUCACCUCUUUGUCUAUUUGUUCUGUAGAGAAAACAAGUGUCAUUGCUUUUGUCUUCUCCAUCUAGACUUUUGCAGUCCUUAGACUAUAGUUCUCCUUAGCUCUAUUCAAAUAGUGCACUUGCAAGGCGCUGCAUUCUUCUCAAAGUCAGCCAUGAUGCACAUAUUUAUAAUUACAUACACAUAUAAUUGAAUAUGAUUUUAGAGUCUUGAAAAACUGAUCUUCUUUGGCACUAUCCUGAAUGUUUCUGAUUUUCUUAAAGUGCCUGACAAUAUUGAGUAACAAAGCUUACCAUCACCACAUUGCACCAUUAUGUAUUAUUCUGUCUCCAUCAAUGCAGUGACAUCACUGAUACAUCAUACCAACAAGAUUUCUAACCACAACCAUUCAGAGCACUAAUUAGCAUCUAUAUUGAGAAUAUAAGAUUAAUAUUACAAACUUGACUUUACUCAUCUCUCUUUAAGAUUUUGAUUUCUGCACAACCAUAUGCAGAACUCAUGUUUGAGAAGGCACUUAAAAGCUGAAAGGCCCAAUUAUCAGUAAUUAUAAUGCUUGCAUGAUCAAAAUUACAAAUUAUCUUUGUUGAUACAAUUAAAAAUGAGUAAUUUUCUGAGCUUAUGUCACUUUUUUAUAGUUCUGAUUUUCUCUUCUUUCCUAUCAGUUGUUUGUACACUGGAGAUUUUAGCUCUUUACAGGGUGCUACAAUCUGGUUUAUUUUAGUCUUCUCUCCUCUACUGCUUUUUCUUCACUUUAAUUCAUUUAUGUGCAAAUCAGGGAAGAAUUGCUGUAGUAUUGAGAAUGGUCAUUUUAAAAGUCUCUACCUUAAGAGCAAAAUUAAUAUUGCAAAAUGAAUUUUUGAUUUUACAGAAGCAUAUGGGAAUUUAGAUCAAAUUACAUCUCCCAUCCCAAUCUCCUGCUUCUUCAUCAUCUCCUAAAUGUUUUCCUUUCUAUGUUUUUAUAAUAUCUAGGUAAAACUUGUUUAGCAUUUUUUAUUUAAUUAUGGACAUAUUUAGUAUGGACUUUUGUUUCUUUGGUAUAGUUAGUUACACUUGUUUGCAUGAUCUACAUGUUUUUCAGUCUCCAUAUAUACUUGUUAAUAAGGUGAGCAAUAUUCAGGAAUAUUUCAGUAGGCAAUUAAUGAUCAUAAAUUUAUUCACAUUUCAGUAAAUAUUUUUCACAUGAUCAAACAGGAUUUUUUGUUUCUUUUUAAUUUAAAUAUGGCAAAAUAAGCUAGAGAAUCUCAGUGUGAAAACACUGAUACUGAACAUUCUAUUAAAAUAGAAUAAGUUCGUGUAGGGACAUGGAUGAAAUUAGAAAUCAUCAUUCUCAGUAAACUAUCGCAAGAACAAAAAACCAAACACCGCAUAUUCUCACUCAUAGGUGGGAACUGAACAAUGAGAACACAUGGACACAGGAAGGGGAACAUCACACUCUGGGGACUGUGGUGGGGUCGGGGGAGGGGGGAGGGAUAGCAUUGGGAGAUAUACCUAAUGCUAGGUGACGAGUUAGUGGGUGCAGCGCACCAGCAUGGCACAUGUAUACAUAUGUAACUAACCUGCACAUUGUGCACAUGUACCCUAAAACUUAAAGUAUAAUAAUAAUAAAUAAAAUAAAAUAAAAUAAUAAAAAUAAAAAUAAAAUAGAAUAAGUUGAUAAAAGCUCCUCUGUUCAGAAAAACAAAAGAAUGGCAUUUUAUCUCACAUAAAUUUAGGAUGAAAUUUUAAAACAUUCUUUUGACUAAGACUUUAAUUCUUAUAUGCAUCUAAAAUAAAUGUUUUGAGUUAGACUCAGUUUAUAUAGCUUCCUCGUUAGAGUACACAUUUUUUUUCUCAUCCUCCGAAUCUCAAGAGUACAUAUUUCUGACAAGCUUUUCAAUGGUACGAUGGAUUUUAUUUUUCUAUCAUCAACUUUCUAUAUUUAACUAAAGCAUUAGUAUUUCUAGAUUUAGUGAAAUAGCAAAUAUGAAUUAAAAUAUUUAUUUCUAAACAUUAGAUCUAAUUGUAUUUUGAUUUGUUUUGAUAUAUUUAUGUCUCAGAAGAUAUGUUUAAUGAAUUCAUUUCAUCCUCUCAACCCUCAGUUUUGAUAGGUAUCCACAUUUUUACCAUAUAAAACUAGACUGGAUUAAGGAUUUUGCCUAAACCUAUACCAAUACUCUGAAUAAAUGCAGGGUUGGAGAUAGAAUUCAGGUCUUUUAACUUCUAACACACUUUUUUCUCCAUUGCACUACAGAAGCCGUAAGGUCAUAAUGAUGAUCUUUGUAGAGUAAAUAAAAUAUUUUCCUAGAAAUAUAUAUAACAACCCUACUUGAUAGUUUAUAGCCCAAAUGAAUAUAUUUUUCCAAUCAUGGUUUGCAAAAUCAUGUUUGCAAACUUACUUUGAAGACUAUUUCCUGAUUGCCACGGCAGAUAAUUCGUGGCAAAUCAGAAAUAAUAUUUAGUGAGAUUAAUUAUUUUGCACAAUAUAUGUUGUUAUAGCAAUAUCAAAAUCAUUUAAAACAUCAAUAUUGUAUUAAUAGAAAACAUGUCAAUAUCUCAUUAAUUCCUUUUUUAUUUUAUGUUCCUUUUUAUUUUAGAAGCAGUGUUCAUUUUUUUCUGAAGUAGAACGCCAGAGCACAGAACACACAGUUCAAGUUUAAAUUAUUAAAUUGUAUGCAAGAAAUUAUUGCCAUAGCAUAGUCUUGAGGAGAACACCUCUACAGUAUUUCUUGAUCUAAGAACCUGAACAUAUGUUAAUGAAAUUAUUAGAGUAAGUUCUAUCUCAAAAAUUUCUUAUUUUAUGAAUGUUUUCUUCACCUAAUAAACAAUACUAAAAUCCAUAACAGCUGUCUGGCAACAGUGUAAUUAGAGCUUCUUUUAUGUUAGAGAUUCCAUCUACCUCUGCAUCUUAUCUAGCUAGAUACAGUCUUUCUAAACUUUCUCCUUUAUUCCCAUGUAGAGAACAAACAAAAAUCACACCUAAAUUAAAGAUCUGUGGUGAAGGGGAAGAGGGGUUGCUAUUAGGAGUUUUCCCGGUAAAACUGUAAAAACAGUAAUCUGCAUUCAGUAUUUGUUUGCCUAGUUCAUCAAGAUAUUUACCCUAAAAACACAUUUUAAUAAAAAUUUGGGUAAACUCAUGUAUCGCAGUAAAAUCUUUUAUGAAUUGGGUGGGCCCUAAAAACAUCUGUAGUACGUGAUGUGUUUGGUUAGAUUCAGCCAAACCGACACCCGUAUGCUAAGACUGCAUUGUCAUUCUGACAGGAGGCAGGCCUCAGUAGUUGCAGUGAGUGCAUUUACUAAUAUAAGGAUCCUUCUUUGUAGUGACAACAAAAAUGAGAUUGUAACUUAAUCAAAUAUGAGUCAGAUAUAGUAAUUCCUGAUAUUGCAGAUGAAAGAGCAGGGUCUUUUCAAGUGCUUGCUACAACUGACUAAAUUUGAAGCUUUUUAUGUAAAAGUUCUUCUCCCAGAUAUUUUAAACCAGUAUGUUAAUUAUUUCCUAGAAUGAAUAAUUCUCCUUUUUUGAUAGAUUUUUGAAAUUGUUUUACUUACUACUUACAUACUUUGAACAAAUAUGUUUUUCUAAUCCCAGCAUUAAAUUGAAACAAAUAUUUAAAAUAAGAUUGUUGGAAUAAAAGUUAUAGAUAGUCACUUGUUGCUAAUAAAAGACAUUCCUUGGCAACAGCCACAUCCAGCUAACUUUUGCAAGAAUUUUUUAAGGGAUUAGAUUUAGGGGUUAAUGUUUAGAAUUAUUUUUAAAAUAUAAAUUAUAUUUUAGGCUGUAUUUUUGUGAUUUUUAAGUGAAAAAAAUAAAAUGUAGUUGUCUUGUUUAUUCUAUAGAUAUCUUAAUGACCACUGAACAAAUGAUCAUAUUGCCACAUGGUCUAUCAACUAUGGUUACUAUGAUAGUGAAAUAAAGAGGAUAGUUUUGCUUGACACCUAAAUGAUCCAAACAGUUGUUUUUACAUGACUUAAAUCAUGGCUGUAUUAUUUCAUUUUUAAAGAAAAUAAAGUAUAAAAUAAUACAUUUAAAAUACCUGUCAAAGUUUUAAAAUAUAAGAUAGAACCUUCUUUUUUUGCCUUCUUACACAUGAAUGUACUUAAAGUAUUGUUAUGUGAUCUUGGGAUACUUAUUUAUUUUUGAAAUUUUUGUAUAUAUAGCAUUUCUGAACUUAGCAAAUAAUAUGUGUAAAGGAAUUAACCAAAAAUGAAAGAACUGGCAUUUUCAUAUGGAUACAUAUUUUGCUUAAACUAAAUAAAAUAACUUAGAUUUAUUUAAAUCAGGAAUAUUUUACGUUGUUGAUCAUUUUUAAAGUAUAUUUUGUUCAAAUAUUCCUAAUUUGUUUUUCAGCACACUUGUUUAAGUUCUUGCCUUUCAGGUAUACUACAGCGUUAUAUGAACAUAAUGUUUUAAAAAAAUCUUGGUUGUAGUUUCUAAUUUUCACUGCAUAACAAAUUUGAAACCAAAUGUUGAAUUUCUCUGUGAGGGUACUUAUUUUGCCUACAGUUUCAAAUAUAUUUUCAAAUUCAUCUCUUUCUUACUAGACUGUGAGCUCCUUGUGGACAAGGAUGUUAUUUUAGUUAUAAUGACAACUUUAAUAUCUAGCAAAGUGCCAGGCAUAGAGUAUUCCUUUAUUGAAAUGAAUUGAUAGAUAUUGAUUAUUAAAAUGCUACUACAGUAUUCUACGAUGCAGGCUGAAUGUAUAUUACAGUAAUUCUCUGGCUAAUUUUAAAAGUAAGACAUAGAAAACAAAACACCUGUAGCAUUUUCUUUAUUUAAAAUUGAAACUCUGUUUUGAAUCCUUUUUAUUUUGUCAAACAUUCUAUGCAAAUAUUGAAAUAUGCAACAGCUAAACUUUAUGGUACAUAUUAAUUAGUUUUAUUUUCUUUUCAAAAUCAGAAAUGCUGUAUUUAAGCUUCCUGGAAAUGUCGACAAUCAUUUUAAUGACCAAAGGUGCUACUUAUUUUUCAACAUUGACCUUGAUCAUAAGUGCUUCUAUCUGCUGAGCUUUAUUUAUUGUUUUUGGACAGAAAGUUUGGUGGGAAGGUUGCAAUAAAAUCAGAAUCUCUCUUGUCUGAAUUAUGCAGUUUAACCCUGUCCAUGUUCCUCUGUACUCUAUUCUUACUGUAUUUUAGUUAUUGUUUCUUACUUAUCACUAAUUUUUACUGCAGGUCUGUGCUGUUUCUUAGAAAGUACAUGCAUAUAUAUUUCUAUAAUAUGUAAGAAAAAACCUGUAUUGCUUAUUAAAUUAAAAUUAAAAUAAAAAAAUUCAUGUUAAA